CUUCUCGCCUAACGCCGCCAACAUGGUGAGUCUUACUGUUGCGGGCUCCGGGGCCGUCGACCAUGCCGCUCGACCUCCACCUCCGCUGGGAAGCUGAGGCGCCAAACGGCUCCCAGAGGGUCCCGGGAAGCGCAUGGUGUUCAGGCGCUUCGUGGAGGUUGGCCGGGUGGCCUAUGUCUCCUUUGGACCUCAUGCCGGAAAAUUGGUCGCGAUUGUAGAUGUUAUUGAUCAGAACAGGGCUUUGGUCGAUGGACCUUGCACUCAAGUGAGGAGACAGGCCAUGCCUUUCAAGUGCAUGCAGCUCACUGAUUUCAUCCUCAAGUUUCCGCACAGUGCCCACCAGAAGUAUGUCCGACAAGCCUGGCAGAAGGCAGACAUCAAUACAAAAUGGGCAGCCACACGAUGGGCCAAGAAGAUUGAAGCCAGAGAAAGGAAAGCCAAGAUGACAGAUUUUGAUCGUUUUAAAGUUAUGAAGGCAAAGAAAAUGAGGAACAGAAUAAUCAAGAAUGAAGUUAAGAAGCUUCAAAAGGCAGCUCUCCUGAAAGCUUCUCCCAAAAAAGCACCUGGUACUAAGGGUACUGCUGCUGCUGCUGCUGCUGCUGCUGCUGCUAAAGUUCCAGCAAAAAAGAUCACCGCCGCGAGUAAAAAGGCUCCAGCCCAGAAGGUUCCUGCCCAGAAAGCCACAGGCCAGAAAGCAGCGCCUGCUCCAAAAGCUCAGAAGGGUCAAAAAGCUCCAGCCCAGAAAGCACCUGCUCCAAAGGCAUCUGGCAAGAAAGCAUAAGUGGCAAUCAUAAAAAGUAAUAAAGGUUCUUUUUGACCUGUUGACAAAUGUAUUUAAGCCUUUGGAUUUAAAGCCUGUUGAGGCUGGAGUUAGGAGGCAGAUUGAUAGUAGGAUUAUAAUAAACAUUAAAUAAUCAGUUCCUUUUUUUUUUUUUUUUUUUUUGAGAUGGAGUCUCGUUCUGUUGCUCAGGCCGGACUGCAGUGGCGCUAUCUCGGCUCACUGUAAGUUCCACCUCCCGGGUUCAUGCCAUUCUCCUGCCUCAGCCUCCUGAGCAGCUGGGACUACAGGUGCCCGCCACCGCGCCUGGCUAAUUUUUUGUAUUUUUAGUAGAGACGGGGUUUCACCGUGUUAGCCAGGAUGGUCUCGCUCUCCUGACCUCGUGAUCCGCCCGCCUCGGCCUCCCAAAGUGCUAGGAUUGCAGGCAUGAGCCGCCGCGCCUGGCCUAAAUAAUCAGUUCUUUAAUCUCACUCUCUGCCCAUACUUGGAUAGGUAGUGCAAAAUCAUUGCAGUCAUAAUUGAUCAUGUCAUGAGAAAUCAUGAUAACUUAGAACACCAAGUGACACAAGUGACAUUUUUUUCUUAUGGUCACCUUGGCUUCAGAACAUCUUUUUUCCUUGUACAAAUAUGUUUGCCAUAAAUAGGUAAAGUGACAGCCUCUUGAUGCUCAAGAGUCUAGCAGAUUUAUUUUAUUUAUUUAUUUUUUUUUUUUGGAGACAGAGUCUUGCUGUGUUGCCCAGGCUGGAGUGCAGUGGUGCGAUCUCAGCUCCCUCCACCUUCCGGGUUCAAGUGAUUCUCCUGCCUUGGCUUCCCAGGUAGCUGGGACUACAGGCGCCCACCACCAUGCCCAGCUAAUUUUUUUUGUAGAGACUGGGUUUCACUAUGUUGGCCAGGCUGGUUUUGAACUCCUGACCUCGUGAUCCGCCUGUCUCGGCCUCCCAGAGCGGGGGAUUAUAGGCAUGGGCCACUGCACUUGGCCUUUUUUUGUUUUUUUGAGACAGAGUCUUGAUCUUAUCACCCAGGCUGGAGUGCAGUGGCACGAUCUUGGCUCAGCGCAACCUCUGCCUCCUGGGCUCAAGCGGUUCUCCUGCUCAGCCUUCUGAGUAGUUGGGACUAUAGGUGUGUGCCACCACGUCUGGCUAGUUUUUGUAUUUUUAGUGGAGAUGGGGUUUCACCAUGUUGGCCAUGCUGGUCUCGAGCUCCUGACCUCAGGUGAUACACCCGCCUUGGCCUCCCAAAGUGCUGGAAUUACAGGUGUGAGCCACUGUGCCCGGCCUGCAAAUUUUCUUAUAAAAAGUAAACUAGGAAAAUAGGGCAAGUAUAAAAAUUGCAGGUUGAGCAUAUUUCUAAUCCAAAAAGCUCUAACCUCUGAAACUGAGCUAUGACACUACAAUUUAAAAAUCCCUAGCCUACCCGCAUGGUGGGUUAUGGUCAAAAUACAGGUACACAGCACUAUUCAGUGUCCCUGAGGAAGAAAUAGUUAACCUUCAGGGUACAUGUAUAUGAAGCAUAAAUGAAUUUCCUGUAUAGACCUAGGUCCCAUCCCCAAAGUGUCAUGUAUAUGCACUUAACUCCAACAUCAGAACACAUCUCGUCCUAAGUGUUUCAGAUAAGAGAUACUUAUCCUGUGUAUAGUAGGUUGGACUUCUGUUUCUCUCUACCACAAGAUACAGGUAAUUUGGGGCAGUAAAAGAUCCUGGAUAGAUUUAAAAAUACUACAAAGCUGUACAUGAAACAGGAUUACUUUUUUUUUUUUUUUUGAGACAGAGCCUUACUCUUGCCCAGGCUGGAAUGUAGUGGCACGAUCUCAGCUCACUGCGACCUCCACCUCCCAGGUUCAAGUUGUUCUGCCUCAGCCUCCCAAGUAGCAGGGGUUAAAUGCGUGUACCACCAUGCCCCUCUAAUAUUGUAUUAGAGAUGGGGUUUUGCCAUGUCAGCCAGACUGGUCUUGAACUCCUGACCUCAGGUGAUCUGUCCGCCUUGGCCUCCCAAAGUGCUGGGAUUACAGGCGUGAGCCACCGCUUCUGGCCAGGAAUACAUUUUAAAUAAAUUUGUUUCCUAACCAAAAGCUAGCUUCAGGCGUCACUGGGGUAAAGGAAAAAGCACAUUGAUUUGCUUGAUAAUAGGCAAGUGGUAUGGUGUAAUAAGGAAAAUAUGGAUGAUUUCGGAUUACCUGUUCUACUCUGGGAGGUAGAGAAUUGUCUAGAGAAAGUGGCAUCUAUACCUAAAAUAAGAAGAAGGUGGUGUAAGGGGAAGAAUGACACGAGAUAGGAAAUAAACGAACUGAUAGUGUAGAGGACUGGCUCGGGACCACAUCAAGGAAGUAGGUUAGUGGUUAGAUCGUGUAGGGGAACACGGGAAGCUACUGAGGGUUUUUUAAAAUGGCGUGAUAUCUCAGAUUUAGAUCAUUGAACUGUUAAGACUGAAUCUUAUGGGAUCAAGACUGGGAAUGCUCGGGUUGGCAGUAUGAAGUUUGGCAGUAAUCCAAGGAAGUGACAGUGGUAAUGCCAUUUAGGUGGUCUUGAUCAUGCAUUGGACUGCAGAAAUAAGGGAGAAAACAAUGUGUCAGGGUUUCUGGUUUGUACCUCUGGUUCAUUGGUUGUGAGGGAACAUGAGGCAGGGUAAAGUUUAUCUAGGUAAAAUGAGUUAGUUUUCAUGUAGACUAUCUGGGUGUAUAUGCAAAGACUGCAGACAAUCUAUACUAAAAUCCUGGCUCUGCCUCUUGAAAGCUAUGUAGUUUAGGCACAUAGUCAAAAUCCAGUUUCCUCAUCUAUGUGGUACGCUUCAGAGUAGUUAAUCAUGAUAUGUAGUCCAGUGACUGGUUCCCUUGGUAAGAGCUGUGAUAAUGACACAAGGAGGAGAGGUUUCAGGACAGACUUGGGAUUCAUGAAUAUGUAAGUGGUCACUGAUUCCCCAGGGGUAGGAUGACAACAAUCAAGAGACGAAUAGAGGUUGGAAAGGAGUCAUGAGGGGUGGGAAACUAGCAGGGGCACAUGGAAGCUAGGGAAAGAAUUUUGCUUGAGAUCGUCAAAGUGAGGGGAAGAGGGUAGUAAGCAAAGGAGAAAUGUUAUAUGGGGUUCGGAGGUUUUGUGUUUGUAAAUCUGGAGUGAUGGGCAUGUUCAAAUGCUUCUGGGAAAGGAGCUAAUAGGAGAGAAACUUAGCCCUUCGAAAAACAGGAAGGGAUGGAUCCUAGGGGAGAGGAGGAAGGAUUGGCUUUAGAGGAAAGAUGUCCUUUACGUGAGGAAAAGGAAGAAAAGGUGGGUUUAGAUACUAAAUCUGUAGGUUUGCUGUUAGGAAAUUAAGGACUUUUCACCUUUAUCUCUGAAAUUUCUCUGGAGUUAGCAAGGCAAGGUCAUACACUGAGAAGGAGGGAUGAGGCAGUGUAGAUUUGCAGACAUACAGGUUGUAAUUCCUUAUGGAGGAAAGGGGAGAGCACUUUUGUCAGACUGCCUGUGGCUUUGAGAGCCCUUUGGCUACAGUCCAUGAGGUGCUCAGAGGAUGAGAAAGCUUCAGGGUAGAAGCAGUAUUCAAGCUGCACCUAGAAAACAGUGCAAUACAGAACAGUGGAAAUUGGAAAUUCCAAUCUUGGAAUCUCUAGGAAAGUAACUGAGGCAUACGAUGCCUGAAAAGGAGUAGAAAAUAAAAUUAAUAAGGUGGGACCAUAUGAUAAGAGAUUUGAGGCCGGGCACUGUGGCUCACACCUGUAAUCCCAGCACUAUGGGAGGCUGAGGCAGGCGGAUCACCUGAGGUCAGGGGUCCGAGACCAGCUUGGCCAACAUGGUGAAACCCCGUCUUUACUAAAAAUACAAAAAUUAGACAGGCAUGGUGGAGCAUGCCUGUAAUCCCAGCUACUUGGGAGGCUGAGGCGGGAGAAUCGCUUGAACCCAGGAGGUGGAGGUUGCAGUGAGCUGACAUUACGCCAUAGCACUCCAGCUUGGGCGACAGAGGGAGACUCUGUCUCAAAAAAAAGACUUGAGCAAGGGCGUAAUCUUCAGGAAGGUCAGUCUGGUAGCAUAGUGUGGAUUGGGUUGGGGGAUGGGGAAGGAGAGCAGAAAAUUAUUGAAAUAUCCAGGUGCAUAAAAGUCUACUUUGAUUAUGGAGAACUACACACUUGUUCAGUCACCCUCAUUGGAGACGGGGGAUGGCAUACGAAAAGAAUGCUGAUUUCAGGCUGGGCACGGUGGCUCAUGCCUUUAAUCCCAGCACUUUGGGAGGCUGAGGCAGGUGAAUCAGGGGUUCAAGACCAGCCUGGCCAAUGUGGUGAAACCCUGUCUCUACUAAAAAUCAAAAAAAAAAAAAAAAAAAUGGCUGAUUUCAGAGUCAUAUUCAGGUUUAAAUUCUGUCAUUCAGCCCAAACUCAUUACUUUAUGUUACUUAUGGGAACCUCAUCUAAAAAGCAAGGAUCCUGAUACCUGCCUCAUAUUGUGGCAAGGAUCAAAUGAGUCAAAUAAGAUGCUUGUGAAAGUGAGGACAGGAUCUAUCCUCAACACCUAGUGCAAUUCUUUUUACACAUUAGGUACUUAGUAAUUUGGGUUGAAUUGUGUUGAACUAACCUGGCGGUAUAGGCAAAAUUUGGAAGUUUGGUUUUCAGAAAGUCUUGACUUCCUCUUAUCUCUAAGUAAUUGGCAUGUCCUCUAAUUCAUAUUUUCCCCCCUCAUCUGUUGGGUGAAAUACUGUUUAUCCUUUAGUACUAAAAUUAAAAGUUACCUCAUUCUUCUAGCUAGCUGAUUUUUUUUUUUAAUCUAGGCUAAAUCAUGAAUACAUUUACAUUUAAAUAAAAUAUUACAGUUGAAAGUAAAGGGUCCUUUCAUUAUCUCCACUUCCAAUUCCAGUACCCUGUGUAAAGGAAAACAUAUACAUCUUGCAGACAUUUUUUAAUGUGUUUGUAAUAUAGGUACAUAAAAAUAUAUGUGCUUGUUUUAAGCAAAUUUCAUACUCUGCAACUUGCCUUUUUUCUUAAUACGUUCUGGAGAUCUUAUCUAGUCAGCCUCUAAAUUAGAGUUCUUCAGAAAACCAAUGGGAUGGAUGAAUGGACUCAAGAGAUUGUGGAAACCAAGAAGUCCCACAAAAUACCAUCUGCAAGCUGGAGAACCAGGAAAGCUGAUUGGGAUAAUUCAAACUGGGUCCAGAGGCCUGAGAACUGGAAGGGCCAGUGGUGUAAGUCCUGGUCUGAGACCAAAGGCUUGAUCAAGAAUCAAGAGCAUCAACAACCGAGGGCAGGAGAGGAUGGGUUUCCCAGAUUAAAAAAGCAAAUUCACGCUUCCUCCCCCAUUUUGUUCUAUUUGAACCUUCCGUGGAUAGGAUGAUGCCCACCUGCAUUGGUGAAGGUCAUCUUUACUCAGUCUACCCAUUCAAAUGCCAAUCUCUUCCAGAGGUAAUCUCACAGAUUUAGAAAUGUUUCGCCAGCUAGCUGAACAAUCCUUAGCCCAGUCAAGUGCACACAUAACCAUAACAAUUCUUACUAAUCUACCUCAUUCUUUUUUAUCUUCUGCAUAAUAAUCCACAACAUGAAUGUUCACGUUUGACCUCUAUUGAUAGACAUUUCGGAUGAUGCCAAUUUCUUUUUCUGGUUUUUGUUUUUUGUGUGUGUGUGUUUUUUUUUUUUUUGAGACGAGGUCUUGCUCUCGCCCAGGCUGGAGUGCAGUGGGUGGGGUGAUCUCGGCUCACUGCAACCUCUGCCUCCCGGGUUCAAGCAGUUCUCCUGCCUCAACCUCCUGAGUAGCUGGGAUUACAGGAGUGUGCCACCACACCUGGCUAAUGUUUGUAUUGUUAGUAGAUACAGGGUUUCACCCUGUUAGCCAGGAUGGUGGAUGGGCAUUUGAAUGGGUAGACUGAGUGAUCCUGACCUCGUGAUCCACUCCCCAGUCUCCCAAAGUACUGGGAUUACAGGCGUGAGCCACGGCACCAGGCCCUCUUUUUCUAUUUAAACAGUGCUUCCGUGAAUGUCCUUGUGUACACCUCCUUCUGUACACAAUGAUGUUUAUCUGAUGCACAUUGCCAAUCAGUGCACUUGCUGGAUUGAAGAAUGUGAGUGUUUGUAUCACUCUUUCAGUAGGCUGUACCAAUUUAGACUUGCUCUACCAAUUUAGAUUUCCAUCAGCAGUAAACAAAGACAUUCCUGCCUGGCAGUCUUGAACUCCUGCUAUUAUCUCUUAAAUUUUUGCCAGUGUGUGAAAAGUAGUAUCUUACUUUAACUUGUAUUUUCCUGGUCCAAUAGUGCACUAAAUGCCCGAGUUCUGUAUUUAUUCUAUUUGGAUAGCCAUUAGAUAGCCAUUAAGUCCACUCAUAGAGUUAUUUUAAAUGUUUUCCUUUAGUUUCCAACCACAUUUUCAAAUAAAAUUUAGAAUUAGCUUGUCAA